AACUCCAGGCAGUCCUUCCAGCCAUGUGGGUUCAGCGGAAAGAGAAGCAAAACCACUCUUCCUAAAAUGUUAGAAGCUGCUCUUCGCUUACCUUGGGGCCUUUGCAUUGGGAGCUGUUUUUCACAUCAAAGAAUAUGUGCUGAAUGGAAUUUUAGUAUUUUGCUGUCGUUUUAAUAUUUUCGUCUGGUCUUCCUCAGUUCUUCCAGACGCUUUCUGAGAGAAUGGGGGCAGGAGCUCUAGCCAUCUGUCAAAGUAAAGCAGCGGUUCGGCUGAAAGAAGACAUGAAAAAGAUAGUGGCAGUGCCAUUAAAUGAACAGAAGGAUUUUACCUAUCAGAAGUUAUUUGGAGUCAGUCUCCAAGAACUUGAACGGCAGGGGCUCACCGAGAAUGGCAUUCCAGCAGUAGUGUGGAAUAUAGUGGAAUAUUUGACGCAGCAUGGACUUACCCAAGAAGGUCUUUUUAGGGUGAAUGGUAACGUGAAGGUGGUGGAACAACUUCGACUGAAGUUCGAGAGUGGAGUGCCCGUGGAGCUCGGGAAGGACGGUGAUGUCUGCUCAGCAGCCAGUCUGUUGAAGCUGUUUCUGAGGGAGCUGCCUGACAGUCUGAUCACCUCAGCGUUGCAGCCUCGAUUCAUUCAACUCUUUCAGGAUGGCAGAAAUGAUGUUCAGGAGAGUAGCUUAAGAGACUUAAUAAAAGAGCUGCCAGACACCCACUACUGCCUCCUCAAGUACCUUUGCCAGUUCUUGACAAAAGUAGCCAAGCAUCAUGUGCAGAAUCGCAUGAAUGUUCACAAUCUCGCCACUGUAUUUGGGCCAAAUUGCUUUCAUGUGCCACCUGGGCUUGAAGGCAUGAAGGAACAGGACCUGUGCAACAAGAUAAUGGCUAAAAUUCUAGAAAAUUACAAUACCCUGUUUGAAGUAGAGUAUACAGAAAAUGAUCAUCUGAGAUGUGAAAACCUGGCUAGGCUUAUCAUAGUAAAAGAGGUCUAUUAUAAGAACUCCCUGCCCAUCCUUUUAACAAGAGGCUUAGAAAGAGACAUGCCAAAACCACCUCCAAAAACCAAGAUCCCAAAAUCCAGGAGUGAGGGAUCUAUUCAGGCCCACAGAGUACUGCAACCAGAGCUAUCUGAUGGCAUUCCUCAGCUCAGCUUGCGGCUAAGUUAUAGAAAAGCCUGCUUGGAAGACAUGAAUUCAGCAGAGGGUGCUAUUAGUGCCAAGUUGGUACCCAGUUCACAGGAAGAUGAAAGACCUCUGUCACCUUUCUAUUUGAGUGCUCAUGUACCCCAAGUCAGCAAUGUGUCUGCAACCGGAGAACUCUUAGAAAGAACCAUCCGAUCAGCUGUAGAACAACAUCUUUUUGAUGUUAAUAACUCUGGAGGUCAAAGUUCAGAGGACUCAGAAUCUGGAACACUAUCAGCAUCUUCUGCCACAUCUGCCAGACAGCGCCGCCGCCAGUCCAAGGAGCAGGAUGAAGUUCGACAUGGGAGAGACAAGGGACUUAUCAACAAAGAAAAUACUCCUUCUGGGUUCAACCACCUUGAUGAUUGUAUUUUGAAUACUCAGGAAGUCGAAAAGGUACACAAAAAUACUUUUGGUUGUGCUGGAGAAAGGAGCAAGCCUAAACGUCAGAAAUCCAGUACUAAACUUUCUGAGCUUCAUGACAAUCAGGACGGUCUUGUGAAUAUGGAAAGUCUCAAUUCCACACGAUCUCAUGAGAGAACUGGACCUGAUGAUUUUGAAUGGAUGUCUGAUGAAAGGAAAGGAAAUGAAAAAGAUGGUGGACACACUCAGCAUUUUGAGAGCCCCACAAUGAAGAUCCAGGAGCAUCCCAGCCUAUCUGACACCAAACAGCAGAGAAAUCAAGAUGCCGGUGACCAGGAGGAGAGCUUUGUCUCCGAAGUGCCCCAGUCGGACCUGACUGCAUUGUGUGAUGAAAAGAACUGGGAAGAGCCUAUCCCUGCUUUCUCCUCCUGGCAGCGGGAGAACAGUGACUCUGAUGAAGCCCACCUCUCGCCGCAGGCUGGGCGCCUGAUCCGUCAGCUGCUGGACGAAGACAGCGACCCCAUGCUCUCUCCUCGGUUCUACGCUUAUGGGCAGAGCAGGCAAUACCUGGAUGACACAGAAGUGCCUCCUUCCCCACCAAACUCCCAUUCUUUCAUGAGGCGGCGAAGCUCCUCUCUGGGGUCCUAUGAUGAUGAGCAAGAGGACCUGACACCUGCCCAGCUCACACGAAGGAUUCAGAGCCUUAAAAAGAAGAUCCGGAAGUUUGAAGAUAGAUUCGAAGAAGAGAAGAAGUACAGACCUUCCCACAGUGACAAAGCAGCCAAUCCGGAGGUUCUGAAAUGGACAAAUGACCUUGCCAAAUUCCGGAGACAACUUAAAGAAUCAAAACUAAAGAUAUCUGAAGAGGACCUAACUCCCAGGAUGCGGCAGCGAAGCAACACACUCCCCAAGAGUUUUGGUUCCCAACUUGAGAAAGAAGAUGAGAAGAAGCAAGAGCUGGUGGAUAAAGCAAUAAAGCCCAGUGUUGAAGCCACAUUGGAAUCUAUUCAGAGGAAGCUCCAGGAGAAGCGAGCGGAAAGCAGCCGCCCUGAGGACAUUAAGGAUAUGACCAAAGACCAGAUUGCUAAUGAGAAAGUGGCUCUGCAGAAAGCUCUGUUAUAUUAUGAAAGCAUUCAUGGACGGCCGGUAACAAAGAACGAACGGCAGGUGAUGAAGCCACUAUACGACAGGUACCGGCUGGUCAAACAGAUCCUCUCCCGAGCUAACACCAUACCCAUCAUUGGUUCCCCCUCCAGCAAGCGGAGAAGCCCUUUGCUGCAGCCAAUUAUCGAGGGCGAAACUGCUUCCUUCUUCAAGGAGAUAAAGGAAGAAGAGGAGGGGUCAGAAGACGAUAGCAAUGUGAAGCCAGACUUCAUGGUCACUCUGAAAACCGAUUUCAGUGCACGAUGCUUUCUGGACCAAUUCGAAGAUGACGCUGAUGGAUUUAUUUCCCCAAUGGAUGAUAAAAUACCAUCAAAAUGCAGCCAGGACACAGGGCUUUCAAAUCUCCAUGCUGCCUCAAUACCUGAACUCCUGGAACACCUCCAGGAAAUGAGAGAAGAAAAGAAAAGGAUUCGAAAGAAACUUCGGGAUUUUGAAGACAACUUUUUCAGACAGAAUGGAAGAAAUGUCCAGAAGGAAGACCGCACUCCUAUGGCUGAAGAAUACAGUGAAUAUAAGCACAUAAAGGCGAAACUGAGGCUCCUGGAGGUGCUCAUCAGCAAGAGAGACACUGAUUCCAAGUCCAUGUGAGGGGCAUGGCCAAGCACAGGGGGCUGGCAGCUGCGGUGAGAGUUUACUGUCCCCAGAGAAAGUGCAGCUCUGGAAGGCAGCCUUGGGGCUGGCCCUGCAAAGCAUGCAGCCCUUCUGCCUCUAGACCAUUUGGCAUCGGCUCCUGUUUCCAUUGCCUGCCUUAGAAACUGGCUGGAAGAAGACAAUGUGACCUGACUUAGGCAUUUUGUAAUUGGAAAGUCAAGACUGCAGUAUGUGCACAUGCGCACGCGCAUGCACGCACACACACACACAGUAGUGGAGCUUUCCUAACACUAGCAGAGAUUAAUCACUACAUUAGACAACACUCAUCUACAGAGAAUAUACACUGUUCUUCCCUGGAUAACUGAGAAACAAGAGACCAUUCUCUGUCUAACUGUGAUAAAAACAAGCUCAGGACUUUAUUCUAUAGAGCAAACUUGCUGUGGAGGGCCAUGCUCUCCUUGGACCCAGUUAACUGCAAACGUGCAUUGGAGCCCUAUUUGCUGCCGCUGCCAUUCUAGUGACCUUUCCACAGAGCUGCGCCUUCCUCACGUGUGUGAAAGGUUUUCCCCUUCAGCCCUCAGGUAGAUGGAAGCUGCAUCUGCCCACGAUGGCAGUGCAGUCAUCAUCUUCAGGAUGUUUCUUCAGGACUUCCUCAGCUGACAAGGAAUUUUGGUCCCUGCCUAGGACCGGGUCAUCUGCAGAGGACAGAGAGAUGGUAAGCAGCUGUAUGAAUGCUGAUUUUAAAACCAGGUCAUGGGAGAAGAGCCUGGAGAUUCUUUCCUGAACACUGACUGCACUUACCAGUCUGAUUUUAUCGUCAAACACCAAGCCAGGCUAGCAUGCUCAUGGCAAUCUGUUUGGGGCUGUUUUGUUGUGGCACUAGCCAAACAUAAAGGGGCUUAAGUCAGCCUGCAUACAGAGGAUCGGGGAGAGAAGGGGCCUGUGUUCUCAGCCUCCUGAGUACUUACCAGAGUUUAAUUUUUUUAAAAAAAAUCUGCACUAAAAUCCCCAAACUGACAGGUAAAUGUAGCCCUCAGAGCUCAGCCCAAGGCAGAAUCUAAAUCACACUAUUUUCGAGAUCAUGUAUAAAAAGAAAAAAAAGAAGUCAUGCUGUGUGGCCAAUUAUAAUUUUUUUCAAAGACUUUGUCACAAAACUGUCUAUAUUAGACAUUUUGGAGGGACCAGGAAAUGUAAGACACCAAAUCCUCCAUCUCUUCAGUGUGCCUGAUGUCACCUCAUGAUUUGCUGUUACUUUUUUAACUCCUGCGCCAAGGACAGUGGGUUCUGUGUCCACCUUUGUGCUUUGCGAGGCCGAGCCCAGGCAUCUGCUCGCCUGCCACGGCUGACCAGAGAAGGUGCUUCAGGAGCUCUGCCUUAGACGACGUGUUACAGUAUGAACACACAGCAGAGGCACCCUCGUAUGUUUUGAAAGUUGCCUUCUGAAAGGGCACAGUUUUAAGGAAAAGAAAAAGAAUGUAAAACUAUACUGACCCGUUUUCAGUUUUAAAGGGUCGUGAGAAACUGGCUGGUCCAAUGGGAUUUACAGCAACAUUUUCCAUUGCUGAAGUGAGGUAGCAGCUCUCUUCUGUCAGCUGAAUGUUAAGGAUGGGGAAAAAGAAUGCCUUUAAGUUUGCUCUUAAUCGUAUGGAAGCUUGAGCUAUGUGUUGGAAGUGCCCUGGUUUUAAUCCAUACACAAAGACGGUACAUAAUCCUACAGGUUUAAAUGUACAUAAAAAUAUAGUUUGGAAUUCUUUGCUCUACUGUUUACAUUGCAGAUUGCUAUAAUUUCAAGGAGUGAGAUUAUAAAUAAAAUGAUGCACUUUAGGAUGUUUCCUAUUUUUGAAAUCUGAACAUGAAUCAUUCACAUGACCAAAAAUUGUGUUUUUUUAAAAAUACAUGUCUAGUCUGUCCUUUAAUAGCUCUCUUAAAUAAGCUAUGAUAUUAAUCAGAUCAUUACCAGUUAGCUUUUAAAGCACAUUUGUUUAAGACUAUGUUUUUGGAAAAAUACGCUACAGAAUUUUUUUUUAAGCUACAAAUAAAUGAGAUGCUACUAAUUGUUUUGGAAUCUGUUGUUUCUGCCAAAGGUAAAUUAACUAAAGAUUUAUUCAGGAAUCCCCAUUUGAAUUUGUAUGAUUCAAUAAAAGAAAACACCAAGUAAGUUAUAUAAAAUAAAUUGUGUAUGAGAUGUUGUGUUUUCCUUUGUAAUUUCCACUAACUAACUAACUAACUUAUAUUCUUCAUGGAAUGGAGCCCAGAAGAAAUGAGAGGAAGCCCUUUUCACACUAGAUCUUAUUUGAAGAAAUGUUUGUUAGUCAGUCAGUCAGUGGUUUCUGGCUCUGCCGAGGGAGAUGUGUUCCCCAGCAACCAUUUCUGCAGCCCAGAAUCUCAAGGCACUAGAGGCGGUGUCUUAAUUAAUUGGCUUCACAAAGACAAAAUGCUCUGGACUGGGAUUUUUCCUUUGCUGUGUUGGGAAUAUGUGUUUAUUAAUUAGCACAUGCCAACAAAAUAAAUGUCAAGAGUUAUUUCAUAAGUGUAAGUAAACUUAAGAAUUAAAGAGUGCAGACUUAUAA